ACAUCCUGGAAGAGUGGCCUAGGACAGCUCCUCUCCUGCCAGAGCUAGGCAGGCGCCGAAGUAGCCGCAUGGCCCCGUCAGAAGACCCCAGGGACUGGAGAGCCAACCUCAAAGGCACCAUCCGUGAGACAGGCCUGGAGACCAGCUCCGGUGGGAAGCUGGCUGGCCAUCAGAAGACCGUCCCCACGGCUCACCUGACUUUUGUUAUUGACUGCACCCACGGGAAGCAGCUCUCCCUGGCAGCAACCGCAUCACCACCCCAAGCCCCCAGUCCCAAUCGAGGGCUUGUCACCCCACCAAUGAAGACCUACAUCGUGUUCUGUGGGGAAAACUGGCCCCAUCUGACUCGGGUGACCCCCAUGGGUGGGGGAUGCCUUGCCCAGGCCAGGGCCACCCUGCCGCUCUGCAGAGGGUCUGUGGCCUCAGCUUCCUUCCCAGUCAGCCCGCUCUGCCCCCAGGAGGUUCCCGAGGCUAAGGGGAAACCCGUGAAGGCUGCGCCUGUGAGGUCUUCAACUUGGGGAACAGUCAAGGACUCACUGAAAGCCCUCUCCUCUUGUGUCUGUGGGCAGGCCGAUUAGCUGGAAGGGCCGGGCUCUGAUGCCCAGAGGCUGCAAUUCCCAGGGCCUGGCCCUGCUUCCCCAGCUAAGCAGGAGUCUUUUGUGCUUGAGCCAAGGAAACAUCAUUAGAUCCGCUAAGGGGCAUCUGAAACAUCCGUCGAGUGGCAGAGGCAGGAUAAGUCACCUGCACAUGAAGAGACUCAUUCAUUCAUACAGCAAAUAUUACUGGUACAUCUUCCACAUGCCAGGCCCUGCAAAGUGCUGGGGAGAUACCAUGGUUUUCCUGGAGCUGGUAUUUUUGGGGUGGAGGGAACCCACCCUGAAUAAAUAAAGUAACCCAAUAAAUAAAGAAGAUGAUUUUGAACAGCGAUGAAUGCUCUGCAGGAACUGAAACAGGAUGCUAGAGGGAGAGUGAUUGGGGUGAAGACCUUUCCUGAUGCAGUGCUUGGUAAGGGCCUCUCUGCGCAGGCAACAAAGUGUGAUCUAAAAGAUGAGAAGGGGCCAGCCCUGAGAAAAUCCACCCUCCCCAGGGCCACCUGCUGUCAUCUUACCCCAGGGCAGGCCAGAGCAGUGGUCAGAAUGCCCCAGCAUGACGGGGAGGGGCAACGGGUUUCUUGCUGCCAUCUUGGCUCAGAGGCGAGUGUGUAGGUCACUGCAAAGGCAGGGGAUACCACGUGGGGAGACUCGAGGGCCAUGCCAGUUGGGGCUGGGAGGCUCAGGGAAGUUGGCUCCAGGAGACUCCAUCCCAUAAGGCAGCCCAGGUGGGACCUGGGGAUCUGAGAUGGGAAAUAAGGGGAUCUGGCUUCUCAAAAGGGAGGGAGGUACUCAAAAAUAGAGUAUCAUGUUUGAACGAAUGAAAACAAGACAUGUUAUUUAUUGAGCAUCUACUGCAUACCAGGCUCAUGCUGCCCUCUAGGGAUAGCAAAAAAAAAAAAAAAAGGUGGGGGGAGGAGGUUCACCCCUCAGGGCAAUCGUGUUCCCUGAGCAGGAGGUGGAGUUACUGGUGUGGGUGUGAAGGUGUCUGUGAGUCUAAGGCAUGCACAGCACUGUGAGAAACCCUAAAGCAACCUAUUUAAGGAAGUCAGUCUCAAAGCUCCCAGAUAAAAAUCACUGGGUUUUUCUGUAUUUAUUUUAGAGACAGAGUCUCACUCUAUCACCCAGGCUGGAGUGCAGUGGAACAAUCACAGCUCACUGCAGCCUCAAACUCCUGGGCUCAAGUGAUCCUCCUGCCUCAGCCUCCCGAGUAGCUGAGACUAUAGGUGCACCACUACGCCCAGCUUGACUUCUUUUAGUAGAGAAGAGGUCUCACUGUGCUGCCCAGGCUGGUCUUGAACUCCUGGCCUCAAGCUAUCCUCCCGCUUCAGCUUCCCUAAGUGCUUGGAUUAUAGGUGUGAGCCACCGUAUCUGGUCAUUAAUUUAUUCAAUGACUAUUUUACUAGGUUCCUACAAAUACUAGCUGCUAACAUUUAACAUGUAAUUGACCAUUUACUCUGUGUCAGAGAAACAACAUGGGCACUGUAUUUGUGACCAUUUUAUAGAUUAGAGAGCUGAGGCACAGAGAGGUUGAAGAAUGGACUCAAAGUUCCAUAGACUGGUACCAUUGAGAUUAGAACUCAGGCAAGUCUGGUGCCCAUAUUCUUGCUUGUAACUGUAAGGUAUAUACCCUCUCAUCCUGGUAGCGUCUCUUCUAGGCAGAGGGGACACACAGAGGAUAAAUGUAACCCUGUCCUCAAGGAGCUCACAGCCAGGUGGGGGAGGCCAGAAAGAAAGCACACAAUUGCCAUAGCUUCUGAGAAGUGCAACAGUAAGGGCAACACAGAAUGAUGCUGGAGGACAACCAGCCCACUCUAGAGAGAGGAGAUCAGGGAGGACUUCCUGCAGGAAGUGAUGCCGAAAAUGAGAUCUGACCGGUGACUAAGCUAUACAAAAGGGUGGGGUGGGGGAGCAAGUGGGGAGUGCUCUGGGCAGAAGGACCAGUCGUUCAGUCUGGCUAGGGUAAUUGUCAUUCAUUCAUUUAUUCACCAAGUAUUUAUUGGGCAUCCACUGAAUGCCAGGCUUUGGGCUAAACCAUGAGAUGGAGCAAUGAAUAAGACAAUGAGGCCCAGCCACAAAAUAGUUUAUCCUCUAGUUGGGGGAGACAGGCAAUGCACACACACAAAACAAACAGAUCAGAAAGGUGGCAGGAGGCCAGGCGCGGUGGCUCAUGCCUGUAAUCCCAGCACUUUGGGAGGCCAAGGAGGGGGAGGCGGGGGGAGAUCACCUGAGGUCAGGAGUUCGAGACCAGCCUGGCCAACUUGGCGAAAACCCGUCUCUACUAAAAAUAUAAAAAUUAGCUGGGCGUGGUGGUGGGCACCUAUAAUCCCAGCUACUUGGGAAGCUGAGGUGAGAGAAUUGCUUGAACCUAGAAGGCAGAGGUUGCAGUGAGCCGAGAUCUCGCCACUGCACUCCGGCCUGGGUGACAGAGCAAGAGCAAGACUGUCUC